GAGCACACGGGAGAGGAGAAGAGGGAGACCCGCCGCCUCCCUCCCUCCCUAGCUGACUUGCUCCCUCCCGGGCUGCGGCUGCUGCAAAAGCCAGCAGCGGCAGCGGGAGCUGUCCGGAGGCCGGCGUCGAGGUGAGACCCGGGCAGACUGAGGCUGCGGGGUUUGCCGCUGUCUCUGCUAUUCCAUCCUCCCCAUAGGGGCUCUCUCCCCUCUCCCAUCUCAAGAUGGCAGCCAGCAGCUCUGAGAUCUCUGAGAUGAAGGGGGUUGAGGAGAGUCCCAAGGUUCCAGGCGAAGGGCCUGGCCAUUCUGAAGCUGAAACUGGCCCUCCCCAGGUCCUAGCAGGGGUACCAGACCAGCCAGAGGCCCCGCAGCCAGGUCCAAACACCACUGCGGCCCCUGUGGACUCAGGGCCCAAGGCUGGGCUGGCUCCAGAAACCACAGAGACCCCGGCUGGGGCCUCAGAAACAGCCCAGGCCACAGACCUCAGCUUAAGCCCAGGAGGGGAAUCAAAGGCCAACUGCAGCCCCGAAGACCCAUGCCAAGAAACAGUGUCCAAACCAGAAGUGAGCAAAGAGGCCACUGCAGACCAGGGGUCCAGGCUGGAGUCUGCAGCCCCACCUGAACCAGCCCCAGAGCCUGCUCCCCAACCAGACCCCCGGCCAGAUUCCCAGCCUACCCCCAAGCCAGCCCUUCAACCAGAGCUCCCUACCCAGGAGGACCCCACCCCUGAGAUUCUGUCUGAGAGUGUAGGGGAAAAGCAAGAGAAUGGGGCAGUGGUGCCCCUGCAGGCUGGUGAUGGGGAAGAGGGCCCAGCCCCUGAGCCUCACUCACCACCCUCAAAAAAAUCCCCCCCAGCCAAUGGGGCCCCCCCCCGAGUGCUGCAGCAGCUGGUUGAGGAGGAUCGAAUGAGAAGGGCACACAGUGGGCAUCCAGGAUCUCCCCGAGGUAGCCUGAGCCGCCACCCCAGCUCCCAGUUGGCAGGUCCUGGGGUGGAGGGGGGUGAAGGCACCCAGAAACCUCGGGACUACAUCAUCCUUGCCAUCCUGUCCUGCUUCUGCCCCAUGUGGCCUGUCAACAUCGUGGCCUUCGCUUAUGCUGUCAUGGUGAGCCCCAUGGGACCCUAGCCCAGGCCUGCUGUGGCUCCCAGCUUCCCGCCAGCGCUGCAAUAGAGCCUCUGGAGUAAUCAUGCCUUCCUUCCCCUCUCCUCUCUGCAUGGAUCCCACCUCCCCAAUUCCAGGGCCUUUGUUUGCCUCUCCCUAGGACCUAACCCUCUGAGCCACCACUGCCCUGCCCCUUUGGGUGGGAGGGAUAUGGAAACACGUGUCACACAGCCUCGCUGACCUGUGCCCUCCUCCCCCUGCCCCUUCACUCCUCCUUCCUCCCUUACCCGCCAUCUAUGGGGCUGGCCUCUCUCUCUUCUGGAUGACUUUUCCACCUGAUCCCUUCUGGGCUGGCUUCUCCUGACCCCGGCUAUGUGCCUCCACCCCUCGCCCUAACCCCAGUCCCGGAACAGCCUGCAGCAGGGGGACGUGGACGGGGCCCAGCGUCUGGGCCGGGUAGCCAAGCUCUUAAGCAUCGUGGCGCUGGUGGGGGGAGUCCUCAUCAUCAUCGCCUCCUGCGUCAUCAACUUAGGCGGUGAGUGGGGGCUUGGGACAGGCAGGGGAGGAAUGGAAGGGUUGGCAAGGGCAGCUUUACUAACCCCUGCCCCUGCUCUCUCCUGUCUGUCCUCCUUACCUCUCCUUUGUCUCUCCUUGUCUCCCCCUCCCCCCGUCUGUCCUUCCCUCUCCUCUCCCACAGUGUAUAAGUGAGGGGCUCUGCCCCGCAUCCCAAGACUUUUCUUCCUGUUGGGAGCUGCCUUGGGCCCAUCCCUCCCCUGGGGGGAGCCCAACUGAUGGCCCUGGCCCCCACCCCUAAGGACCAAGGGAGCCUGAGCGGCCUUGUUUACAGCUUCUGUCCUGCUCCUGCAUCUUGCCAGGCUCCUCUGCCAACUGUAGGCCUGCCUCAUCCCUGCACUGGUUCCAACCUCCCUGCACUAAUGCCUGCAUCCCCUCCGGCCUCUUGGCCCCCUAUCCCUGCACUUCUGGAAACCUCCCUGCACUCUGGAAACCUCCCUGAACACCUCCCCAACUCUGCGCUCUCAGCCUCCCUGCAUCUCUCCUGGCCUCCCUGCACUUCUUCCAGCCCCCCAAAUUCUCUGGACCUCCACCCUGGCCGCCUCCUCCCAACUUUCAUUGUCUUGGCAUCUCUCAACCCUCAGUCCUCUCUUCCUUCCCUUCUUUAUCAUCUCCCCUUUCCUCUCCACGUCCCGCCCCCUUCCUCUUCCUGCCUCCUCAUCUCCCUUAAGCAUCCUCUUCUCCAACCUCCCGUCACCGUUUACUCUGCAAAAUUGACAGCACUUAGACGAGGCUUGGGGGCAGGGAGCAGUGUUGGGAGAGGGCUCCCCAACCCCAGGCUCGGACUGUUCUCUGCUGGGACCACCCAGGGUCGGACACCCAAGGGUGCCUGGCAGGUCGCAGAGUUGGCAAGCCGGGCCUCGUAUGGGGACUCGGGUGAGGGUGGCGAGUACUGGUUCCGAACGCACGCAGGGGAGAAGGGAGGGACGCGGCGCUGACCCUUCCAGGUCAGCUGGAGUUGACCCGCCCACCUGGGCUUUUCAACCCCAGUCCGCGAGUUUCUUUCUUGAAGGUGUGGGGGCUAGAUUCAUUCACGUGCUUCGUAAUGAAAUAAUCCAAAAAAUAGGACCAAAGCGCCCACUGGCAGGAGCGAGGGCGGGGCGCCGCGCUCUAUAAUUAUUUUCUAAGAUGAUGGGGGAGGUUUGUUGCACGCGACAGCCCGCUGAGGAGGCGGGGACCGAGCUACAACGCGGUUCGGAUUUGGCGGGGGUUUUUUUCCUUAAAAAAAAAAAAAAAAAAAAAAAAAAAGUCUGGGGGAAGAAAAAAACUAAAAUUCUUAAAAAAAAAAAAAAAAGGCUAUUAUCAAACUGAUUUCUCCCUUUUUGUAUGCCGGAUGCUGCAUGAGUCUGAAACACCAAUAAACGGAGACUGCAUGAGA